ACUCCGAGCUUUUCCUCGGCGAGGAGGAGGGCUCAGAGGGUCAGCUGCGCCCCGGCCAGAGCAGGAGCUGCGGGAAGACCCUGGAGAGCAGGGCUGGGAGUGGGGAUCUGGCAGUGUGGGGCCAAGAAAAAGGGCUGGGGCGGAAAUCCAGAGACAGAGGCAGAGAGGGGAGCAUCUGGGAUCGUGGGGAGGGUUCGUGGAGAGUGAGGCAGGGGAAUGGAGGGAGUAGGAGUCUGGGGAAAGUGAGGAUUUUGAAGUGAGAGAGUCCGCUUGGGCUGGGCGUGGAGGGCCGAGGGUGGAGUGGGGCUGAGGGACGAGGUGGGUUAAGGUGCUGGUGGGGAAGGACUAGAGCUUCCAGGAGGGUCUGAAGGCGGAGGUGGAGGUCGGACAGCACAAGUGAGAGUGAGGGGGUCUGCAGGUAGAGCUGGCAUUGGAGGGGUGGGAACGUGGACGGCGGCUGAGCGGGGGGCGCGUGCAGGUCGGAGCCGGCAGGUGAGGAGCCAGGGUCUAAGCUAGGGCCCGGGGUCCAAAGGAAAGGCUUUCAGAUCUGAGCUCCGCGGCUCUGGCGGCGGUGGAGCUGGGAGCCCGCGGUGGCCGGCUGGGGACGGGGGCAGGAGCAGAGGGGUCGCGCCGCGGCCACUGGAACCCGCGGCUGCUGGUCCUGGGCUCGGCGAUGCGGGUGCACCUGGGCGGGCUGGCCGGCGCGGCUGCGCUGACCGGGGCGCUCAGCUUUGUGCUCCUGGCGGCCGCCAUCGGCACGGACUUCUGGUAUAUCAUUGACACCGAGCGGCUGGAGAGGACUGGCCCGGGGGCGCAGGACCUGCUGGGGUCCAUCAAUCGCAGCCAGCCCGAGCCUCUGAGCUCCCACUCCGGCCUCUGGCGGACCUGCCGGGUGCAGAGCCCGUGCACACCGCUGAUGAACCCCUUCAGGCUGGAGAACGUGACAGUCAGCGAAUCGAGCCGGCAACUUCUCACCAUGCAUGGGACAUUUGUGAUUCUGCUGCCGCUCAGCCUGAUCCUGAUGGUUUUUGGGGGGAUGACGGGGUUUCUGAGCUUCCUCCUCCAAGCCUACCUCCUCCUCCUGCUCACUGGAAUUCUCUUCCUCUUUGGAGCCAUGGUGACCCUCGCUGGGAUCAGCGUCUACAUAGCGUAUUCAGCCGCCGCCUUCCGGGAGGCGCUGUGUCUCUUGGAGGAGAAGGCCCUCCUGGACCAGGUGGACAUCAGCUUCGGCUGGUCCCUGGCCCUGGGCUGGAUCAGCUUCAUCGCCGAGCUGCUCACCGGGGCAGCCUUCCUGGCAGCAGCCCGCGAGCUCAGCCUGAGACGGAGGCAGGACCAGGCCAUAUGAGCCUGGGCGCUGGGUCGUGGAGGGGAGGGAGGGGCUUGGCCCCGGAGCUUCACCGACCGAUCUCCAUCGGCUGCGGCCUCUUCUUCCUCAAAGGCCACUCGGGGAGGCCAGGCACCCCCCUCCUUCCCCCACAAAUCCCCGCGGACUAAGCUUGGGGCCUGGCUGUUAUCCUAGUACCUGUGUGCUUAUGUCCGUGUGUGUCCGUGUGGCCUGGAGGAGCCCGAGGGAGUGCCAAACCGCUUCGCGAGAAAUAAAAACGAUCCUUUAAUCACA